GCUUCACACCUUUCCCGCCCUUAAGUAUGUGUACGUUGGGUGCAGAACCGUUUGGUUUUCCCGAGGGGUAGGCAGAAUUUCCAACCCCACGAGCUGCUCCCUCUUUCCGCAAACCUCCUAACCCCGGGGUUUUUCCAUAAAUGUGUUUACUUCGUCCACGCCAGCCUGCGAAGUUCCAAAAUGGAGUCUGGGCCACGCCGGCGUUCUGGGCACGACUACGGUCUCUUGAAAAGGCCAUUCAAUGUCCCUUCUUCAGGAAUUUGGAAAAAGGAUGGAGAGAUCUCUCUGAGCUAGACUCUUCAGUGGAGGAAAUGUUACAACUCAUGGACAGUGGCAUUACCAUCUGCCUUAGGAACGGAGCAGCCUCUGUCUUCAAGAAAAAAGAAUGGAGCACACAAGGAGAAGAAAACAAGCAAGACAGUAAACUAAAAAAGCUGAGUGAAGACAGUUUGACUAAGCAGCCUGAAGAAGUUUUUGAUGUAUUAGAGAAGCUUGGAGAAGGGUCUUAUGGAAGUGUAUUUAAAGCAAUACACAAGGAAUCCGGUCAAGUUGUCGCAAUUAAACAAGUACCUGUUGAAUCAGAUCUUCAGGAAAUAAUCAAAGAAAUUUCCAUAAUGCAGCAAUGUGACAGCCCAUAUGUUGUAAAGUACUAUGGCAGUUAUUUUAAGAAUACAGACCUCUGGAUUGUUAUGGAGUACUGUGGCGCUGGCUCUGUCUCAGACAUAAUUAGAUUACGAAACAAGACAUUAAUAGAAGAUGAAAUUGCAACCAUUCUUAAAUCUACAUUGAAAGGACUAGAAUAUUUGCACUUUAUGAGAAAAAUACACAGAGAUAUAAAAGCUGGAAAUAUUCUCCUCAAUACAGAAGGACAUGCAAAAUUGGCAGAUUUUGGAGUGGCUGGUCAGUUAACAGAUACAAUGGCAAAACGCAAUACUGUAAUAGGAACUCCAUUUUGGAUGGCUCCUGAGGUGAUUCAAGAAAUAGGCUAUAACUGUGUGGCCGACAUCUGGUCCCUUGGCAUUACUUCUAUAGAAAUGGCUGAAGGAAAACCUCCUUAUGCUGAUAUACAUCCAAUGAGGGCUAUUUUUAUGAUUCCCACAAAUCCACCACCAACAUUCAGAAAGCCAGAACUUUGGUCCGAUGAUUUCACCGAUUUUGUUAAAAAGUGUUUGGUGAAGAAUCCUGAGCAGAGAGCUACUGCAACACAACUUUUACAGCAUCCUUUUAUCAAGAAUGCCAAACCUGUAUCAAUAUUAAGAGACCUGAUCACAGAAGCUAUGGAGAUCAAAGCUAAAAGACAUGAGGAACAGCAACGAGAAUUGGAAGAGGAAGAAGAAAAUUCGGAUGAAGAUGAGCUGGAUUCCCACACCAUGGUGAAGACUAGUGUGGAGAGUGUGGGCACCAUGCGGGCCACAAGCACGAUGAGUGAAGGGGCCCAGACCAUGAUUGAACAUAAUAGCACGAUGUUGGAAUCCGACUUGGGGACCAUGGUGAUAAACAGUGAGGAUGAGGAAGAAGAAGAUGGAACUAUGAAAAGAAAUGCAACCUCACCACAAGUACAAAGACCAUCUUUCAUGGACUACUUUGAUAAGCAAGACUUCAAGAAUAAGAGUCACGAAAACUGUAAUCAGAACAUGCAUGAACCCUUCCCUAUGUCCAAAAACGUUUUUCCUGAUAACUGGAAAGUUCCUCAAGAUGGAGACUUUGACUUUAUAGAGCCUUACUGGGCCCGUGCAGAUUUUCCACUUCCUCGGCUGUGGCCCUUGGCAUCUGCGGUUAUAUUCAACAGGAGCACCAACGGUGGCCAAGAAGUCACUAGGAUGGUGGCUAAAGGGGAGGAGCUGAGCUACACCCCACUUGAUGGAACGCAAAGACUGUGGUGAGGUUGGAGAGCAGUGCUGUGCGUCCUUCCUCAGCCUUAACGAGUGCGGGGCAAGGUUAACACAGAUUUCUACACCCUUUUGCUGCAUACACAGACGAGGCCACCUGCAGAUGCCACCACUGCUCAGUGUGAGUUGAGUGUUGGAUGGGAGAGCCAUCUGCUCCAUACACCUCAGGGCCCCUUCUGGGGCCCAAUAACCUCAUGGGAACAGGUAGGGGAUCUCCUAGCCUUCACAAAGGCAACAAACCAAAAUGAGCAAAGAGUUAGCCCUGAAGUCGAAUGGGAUCUUAUUGAUUUUCCUCUGCCUAAUGAUUGUUAAUAGGAGGAAUCUGGAUUCCGUGUACAUAGGUGGAAAUAGUGGAAAUCCCAAAGGAGACAAGCUGAUGAUUUUAAAACUUGAUUCACUUGGAUCAGAACCUAGCUCAAGCAUUUUCCUGAUUGCAUUGUCCCUGCAACUGUCGUCUAUUGUAGCUGACUGCUGAAGAGGAAAUGAAACCAAAUAGAAGGUUGUUUGUAAGCAAUCUCUCUGCUCUUCUUAAAAAUAAAUUAGGGAUAUCAGGAUCGGCUCAUGGCUAGAAUGAGGACAUAGAGAGACAUGCAGAAAUUCUGUUUUUAUAUUGAGGUGAAGAAGUGGGUAGGGAGGGCUUUAAGGAUUAUCUAAUCCAACCUUCUCAUUUUGCAGCAGUGGAAGGUGAGGCUUGGAGAGGCCACAGGAUGUGCCUACAAUCACAGAGCUGGAGGCAAAACCCAGCAGAACCAAGUCAGCCCAGUGGCCUUCCUACCGAUUCACCAUGGCCUUUGGACCGGCCCAUACUCAGUCUAUUUUAAGUAAUGCCAAGAAGUGUCUCUAUGUAUCCCCCAGCAGUAUUCAUGCCCAACCAGCCAGGACACUCAGGGUUCCCCAAUUUACUAUUAGGGAGCCUACUUCGGCAGCAGGGAGAGUGGUACUUUGGGACAGGUUGGGGCUGGCAGGGCAGGCUGACAGAGGUGCUGAGCAGGAAAGCAUGCAGGAGGAAAAUCCUGCAGGGGUGUCUGUUUCACAAGAGUUACAAGAAUACAGGACCAUUCCUUCUACCAAGGAGGCUAGUGGUUCGAGAUCCUAGAAAACUAGGACUCCGCCUUUACCAAGAAUAAACAACAGCUUCUCCUUCCCCAAAUUGCAAAAACAAACAAACAAACAAACAAAAAAAACACCCAGGCUUUCUCAGGAAAUCUGGUCCCCAACUUUGAAUGCCCUCCUUGUUUGCUACUGCAUAUGUAAUUGAAAUGCCUCCAAGAGAUGCAAAUAAUUUUUGUCUAUUUAAUCUGCACACUUUUUGAGGCUGGAGUCCCGAGUGUGUCAGUAUUACUGCCCAUUCCCGAAUCGAGGCACAGAGAUGAAAGUGCAGCAAUCAGACAUAAUGGUUCAGUGCAGCCUGUGUCAAUGCUUGCACAGUAGUGUGUUAAUGAGUGUUAAAACUGACAUCUCAAAUAUGGCAUCCUCAAUUUUAAAAAUUACAGCUCUGUAAGAAGUCAUGCUGUUAAAACACACAAGAAAUACCAGUUACGCCUUCAAGUAGCUAACACACAGCCUGUACAGAUCACCACUAUCCCAAAGUGCAUAACAACUUAUUUUCUUUGAAAUGCGGCAAGAAUUAGCAGGUAGUUCAAUUAUUUGAGUGCUAAGAUAAGUAGAAAUAACAAAUGCAAAUGUUAAAUACCAAUUACUACCUUACGAGCUACAAAUCAGCUUGGCAUUACAACAUGCCCUUCCUCACUCACAAACCCGAGAAAUGUGGGGGUUUGGCAGAAAACACAAACCUAUAACCAAUAUGCAUUUGUGCAACAGACGUGUCACUUCCCAACCCAGCACUUCCAAAAUGCACAUCACAGAUAUCAAAGCCUGGCCCAUAUAUUUGGCCCACUGGCAUUGAAAACAAUAACCUUCAAAUGCUGGGAGUGACACUUCUCUCAAGCUCACAGCUGGAAACAAGUCAUCUCCAGUUUCUACUCUGUCCCCCUAAAGGAGGUUUACAGGUCAGUCUGACAGCCUGGUUGCCAAAGAUGUCACCUCAUAUUUUUACAGAAAAUUAACCUGACUCUCCCUGGUUAGCUUCAGGGACUAAAAGAAACUGCUGGUUAGAUGUUAUCUAGCAAGGUCGAUCAAAGACCCAGUGGAGAGCACCUGUAAACUUCAAACCUUAGUGAGACUUUAGGGGAGAGGAAGAUUAUUUCUCCCUGGGUCACCAUUCAGUCUACAUUCCUUGUGGGAAUUAGCUCCAGGGUUUAAGCCAGCCGGGUUGUUCUUUCUCCCACUUAUCUGAAACCACCACUUGAAAAACUCAAUGCUAUUGGGACAUUCUCAUGCUCAGAAGUGAGUAAAGGUCCAGUUGGGCAAGAUAAUAUUUUAUAUAAGUAUAUAUGUAUGUACAAGAGAUGUUAAAAAGAUAGUCUCUAAAGCACGUUGGGAUUCCUCCAACGAAAGGCACCAGAUAAAUGCAAGUCAUUACCAAAAAGAAAAGUCAAGUUUUCCAGCUUUCACAUCUGCAAAGGGUAACCACUAGGGUACCUCUUUUUUGGUGGUAAGCCUUCUUGUUUAGAAAAAUCUUCAUGAAAGUGACUGAGUUAUUCUGCCUUGUUCCUUGCUUCCACUUUGCAUAAGCUUCCUGGUCAGCGGCCAUGGAUACCAGGCUCAGUGACCCAAUACCAUCAGCCUUGGCAAACUGAUCCGUCCUCAUAAGUCUGUACCACCACCUGCCUUCAGUGCAGCUGGGGAUGAGUCCGUAAAUGUUAUGCCUUCCAGGGCUGGAAGCACCAGCCAAAUCUAAGUGUUCCAUGUGCAAAUUCUGAAAAAUAACUCUGCUCCUCUGAUUCAGUGCCCAGUUGCCUCUAAGUCAUCUCACUUUUCCUGAUGCUUCAGAGACACGGAUGUAGACACUAGGAGACAGCCACCUCCCAGCCUCCCACAAGCCUCCAGUCCAAUGGAAAGAUUUGAACUGGGGGCUCCAGGACACAAGUGGCUAGUGAAUUCAUUCAAUAAAUCACCCACACUGUAGUAGCCAUGACAACUACAAGAACACAAAGCCUUCUGAUAAGAUCCUUGCCACACCUCCAAUGAGGUAAGUAUCAUCUUCAAUCAACUGAAACACAAAAGGACCUCUUAAGAAGAGGCCCAACCUUUGGAUGAAAACCCUGGAUAGCUCCAUGCUCAGACCCCUGGGUUCUAUUGCCUUUUCAAAGAUGGAACAAUAAUGAAAGCCACCUGGAAAACCAUCAGAUUACCUUAAAGAUGAUGGAGAAGAAUUAUCUUAUAGAGGAACCCAGGUUCCCCAUCACAAUGUUAUGUGCUGGUUAACCGAACAAGAGGAGCAGGAGCAUUUUGGAGGAGGAAACAGUCGUCUCCCUUCAAUACAAGUUUGGAAGCUUGAAGGUCUUUUGAAUAGCAUUAAGCUUUUCAAGUUUACAAUUUUUUAUGACAUUUUAUGAACUAGCAGUUUUUUAUUUUACAACUCUUUCCUUUCUCCUGGCCUCUACCCAGUCACCCCCCAUGAAAGGCAGUGGGAAUGCAAGUAAGAACUGCAGUGUUUCCAUCCUGGGUAAGCCACACCACCAUCGUGCACGUCUAUAUUUUGAGUACAUGCUUCCAUACCACCAGGUUUCCAUGUCAUGGCAGGAACUCCAGGGCAAUCACAGCAUCAUAUACAACAUACUAUAUCCUAGAAGCAAAAUUAUCUGACUAAAUUCUGCUUGGAAAUAAAAGGGCUCUCAUUUGAUGAGCUUUCAGAGUAGGCAACAAAAGUAUUUAAGCUACUGCCCUUGCUAGCAACCCAACAACGUUCACCUCAGGGAGACGAUACAACAGUAAACUUCUUUUUAGUUGAGGAAGACAACACGACCUUACUCCUAAACAUCUUAAAAAAUAAAUAUUUCAAAAACAUGCUAAUAUCUUAGACACAGCAAAGUUUGGUCAAAUGGCCUAGAUCAGAAACCUCAUCCGGAAAUACAUUUCUCUACAGUCACCCUAGGAAACAAGGAGGCUUGACUGUGAACCAAGGGGCUCAGCCUGCACUAACUUGGCUUUAAGCACCCUAGGGUUUGGACUAUUUAGCUGAAGCCCCUCUCCCUAACACAUCUGUUCUUGGGAAAAAAAUUCGAUCUUCACUGCAUGUUUAACUAAGUAACAUUCUCUAAAGAGUGACAUUUAUGAGAUGAACAUCAGUGUACAUCGUUCUAAAGAUGAUUGGUGCACCCAUGCAAGCCACGGAACUACAGAUCAUUUAUAAAAACAACUUAGAGACUUGCAUUGGUCAAGUCUGCUUAACUUUGCAUUCUCUUUGUUU